GGGUAGGGCUGCAGCUCCGGAGCCUACGGGAGUGUGACCCUCUCGCCUCCUGGCGGGAAGCUCUUGAGGAGAUAUUUUCUUUUCUAAACACUAAGAAAUUUGAGGAUGGUGGGGCAAAACGACUAACUCCCACUUUCCUGUGACUCUGUAGCCGGAAAAACUGUCAAAAUCUGUGGAUAAAUUUGUGAGACAAGAAGAAGAAUGGCAUCCAGAAUAAAUACAAAUUUCACUUUGAUUCCCAACCAGAAACUUAGACGUAGUAAUCGUCAAACCAGCUGUUAUUCCAAGACCCUUGGCUCAGGCUUUCAACCCAUAUCAACAUUUGGAAAUUUUAAAGCCUUACCAUUGGAAAUAUUCCAGAUAAUUUUAAAAUAUUUGUCAGUGAAGGAUAUCAGCAUGCUAAGCAUGGUGUCCAAAACAGUCAGCCAACACAUUAUUAAUUAUAUCUCAACCUCAUCAGGAAGCAAAAGACUUUUACUACAGGACUUUCAUAACCUUGAGCUGCCUGACAGGAGACAAGACUCUGCUAUACUGGAGCACUACAGAUCUCUAGGUCUACUGUUUAAAAGAUGCACAUUGCUGCUACCCACCAAGGAAAGGCUAAAAUACAUUCACAAGAUACUCACAGAAGUUUCCUGCUUUAAAUUCAAUGGCUGUGCAGCUCCUAUGCAGUGUUUAGGAUUAACAUGUUAUGGCAUGUUUUUACAGACCUUAACAGCAGGUUGGGAUGAACUUGAGUGCCAUCGCGUUUAUAAUUUCUUAUGCGAACUGACUAAUCUCUGCCGCAAGAUACAAAUGGCUGUCUGCAGCAAACCAGGAAGUGCCCAAAAACUGGAGUUAAGAAUCAGACUCUUCUGUAGGAAUGUCCUCCUUGAUCAUUGGACACAUCGAAGUGAUUCUGCUUUUUGGUUGACGCGAAUAUUAAAACCAUGGCCAAUGGUGAAUCAGGCAAGAUUACUGUAUAUCAUCUUUGGGCCAAUAUCUCCUCAAGAUGGACAGGUGGUUUGGCAGGAAAUGAUAGAAGAACCUACAGAUGAAUUCAGUCUGAAAGGUUUGGCUGAUGCCAUUAAGUUACUAUAUGACGCUAGCACUAAAGAGUGGACAGCAGAUGAUGUUAUCAGUCUUGUAGAUGAACUAUCAGUGGUUCCCCGUGAGUGGCUUCUAGAGAAUAAUGCACGUCUCCUAAUGCUAAGUGGAAACAACAUCUGUUUCAGUUUCAUGGCUAGUAAAGCUGUGAAUGGACGCACCAUUGAACUGGCAAGGCUCGUAGUCUUUUUGGCUUUGGUGUGUGAGAAAGAACUGUACUGCAUGGAUUGGACAGUUAAAAUGAUGCAAAAAGUCUGCAAAGUCUUUAGCACUCCAGUGGAAAGAAAGAACUUCCUGCAGAAUGUGGCAAAUGCAUUUGCAUGUGUUAUAAUGGAAAUGCUGCAAUCAAUUAUGUCUGGAGACCGUGAUGAAGAUGACAGAAGCUUUUUGAAUUUGUUCCAUCUUGUACAUGCUCAGGCUAACUUCCAUAAGGAGGUCCUGUAUUUGACCAUGAAUACUCCUCUGUCUACCUAAAUCCUCAGAAAGCCUUGCCUUUAGAGAACGUCACUGAACGAAUGAUUAGAGGAGUGCUACUUUUUCACUCAAAAAAUAGCAUCCAUGGGACUUUUUAUCAUCUAAGUAACCUAAGAAUUCAAAAGCUGGAUAGAAUUUUAGAAGCAACUACGUACAUCAUUAUUAAUAUAAAAAUAACAGGCAGCCUCAAGAAUGUGCUGAGAUUUCUCUGGAAAACAAGCUCUGCCUCUCCGGGUUUUAGUCAACCUAACACCAAACCAAAAUAGAAUGUUAGCUGUUCAAGAAUCUGGGACCAGCCAACCUGUAUGUAUGCAUUUUUGAAGCAAGAGAAAAUUCCAUUUUAUAGUUAGACCCAAAUUCACUAAAUAGUGUGUAUGUUCACUUUGUUUAAGUUGUAUAGACAUAGCCCAGAAUGUUUUGUGAAGAUUUGCAAUAUGGUGUUUUGGAAUGUGUAGAAUACAAAUCACAGUUUUUACUACCUUCUUGGCAUAUGCUUACAAAGAACAUUAUAUUUUGUUCAUGUUUUACAUGAACUAAUGGAUAAAAAACAAAGUAUACAUAUAUGUCUAUAUAUAUAUAUAGACACACACACACAGACAUAUAUUUCCUUCUUUAAGGUAAUCAUACAAAAGGUCUAUACAUACAGGAAGGUAUAUAUUGUCUCAAUGCAAUCAAAUCAUCUUUUACUGGGGAUUCAAAUAAAAUGUAGCAAAUAAGAGAAAAAUAAAAUGAAAGAAAAUAGC